GCAGUGCGCAGGCGUGAGCGGUCGGGCCCCGACGCGCGCGGGUCUCGUUUGGAGCGGGAGUGAGUUCCUGAGCGAGUGGACCCGGCAGCGGGCGAUAGGGGGGCCAGGUGCCUCCACAGUCAGCCAUGGCAGCGCUGCGCUACGCGGGGCUGGACGACACGGACAGUGAGGACGAGCUGCCUCCGGGCUGGGAGGAGAGAACCACCAAGGACGGCUGGGUUUACUACGCCAAUCACACCGAGGAGAAGACUCAGUGGGAACAUCCAAAAACUGGAAAAAGAAAACGAGUGGCAGGAGAUUUGCCAUACGGAUGGGAACAAGAAACUGAUGAGAACGGACAAGUGUUUUUUGUUGACCAUAUAAAUAAAAGAACCACCUACUUGGACCCAAGACUGGCGUUUACUGUGGAUGAUAAUCCGACCAAGCCAACCACCCGGCAAAGAUACGACGGCAGCACCACUGCCAUGGAAAUUCUCCAGGGCCGGGAUUUCACUGGCAAAGUGGUUGUGGUCACUGGAGCUAAUUCAGGAAUAGGGUUCGAAACCGCCAAGUCUUUUGCCCUCCAUGGUGCACAUGUGAUCUUGGCCUGCAGGAACAUGGCAAGGGCGAGUGAAGCAGUGUCACGCAUUUUAGAAGAAUGGCAUAAAGCCAAGGUAGAAGCAAUGACCCUGGACCUCGCUCUGCUCCGUAGCGUGCAGCAUUUUGCUGAAGCAUUCAAGGCCAAGAAUGUGCCUCUUCAUGUGCUUGUGUGCAACGCAGCAACUUUUGCUCUACCCUGGAGUCUCACCAAAGAUGGCCUGGAGACCACCUUUCAAGUGAAUCAUCUGGGGCACUUCUACCUUGUCCAGCUCCUCCAGGAUGUUUUGUGCCGCUCAGCUCCUGCCCGUGUCAUUGUGGUCUCCUCAGAGUCCCAUCGAUUUACAGAUAUUAACGACUCCUUGGGAAAACUGGACUUCAGUCGCCUCUCUCCAACAAAAAACGACUAUUGGGCGAUGCUGGCUUAUAACAGGUCCAAGCUCUGCAACAUCCUCUUCUCCAACGAGCUGCACCGUCGCCUCUCCCCACGCGGGGUCACGUCGAACGCAGUGCAUCCUGGAAAUAUGAUGUACUCCAACAUUCAUCGCAGCUGGUGGGUGUACACACUGCUGUUUACCUUGGCGAGGCCUUUCACCAAGUCCAUGCAACAGGGAGCUGCCACCACCGUGUACUGUGCUGCUGUCCCAGAACUGGAGGGUCUGGGAGGGAUGUACUUCAACAACUGCUGCCGCUGCAUGCCCUCACCAGAAGCUCAGAGCGAAGAGACGGCCCGGACCCUGUGGGCGCUCAGCGAGAGGCUGAUCCAAGAACGGCUUGGCAGCCAGUCCGGCUAAGUGGAGCUCAGAGCGGAUGGGCACACACACCCGCCCUGUGUGUGUCCCCUCACGCAAGUGCCAGGGCUGGGCCCCUUCCAAAUGUCCCUCCAACACAGAUCCGCAAGAGUAAAGGAAAUAAGAGCAGUCACAACAGAGUGAAAAAUCUUAAGUACCAAUGGGAAGCAGGGAAUUCCUGGGGUAAAGUAUCACUUUUCUGGGGCUGGGCUAGGCAUAGGUCUCUUUGCUUUCUGGUGGUGGCCUGUUUGAAAGUAAAAACCUGCUUGGUGUGUAGGUUCCGUAUCUCCCUGGAGAAGCACCAGCAAUUCUCUUUCUUUUACUGUUAUAGAAUAGCCUGAGGUCCCCUCGUCCCAUCCAGCUACCACCACGGCCACCACUGCAGCCGGGGGCUGGCCUUCUCCUACUUAGGGAAGAAAAAGCAAGUGUUCACUGCUCCUUGCUGCAUUGAUCCAGGAGAUAAUUGUUUCAUUCAUCCUGACCAAGACUGAGCCAGCUUAGCAACUGCUGGGGAGACAAAUCUCAGAACCUUGUCCCAGCCAGUGAGGAUGACAGUGACACCCAGAGGGAGUAGAAUACGCAGAACUACCAGGUGGCAAAGUACUUGUCAUAGACUCCUUUGCUAAUGCUAUGCAAAAAAUUCUUUAGAGAUUAUAACAAAUUUUUCAAAUCAUUCCUUAGAUACCUUGAAAGGCAGGAAGGGAAGCGUAUAUACUUAAGAAUACACAGGAUAUUUUGGGGGGCAGAGAAUAAAACGUUAGUUAAUCCCUUUGUCUGUCAAUCACAGUCUCAGUUCUCUUGCUUUCACAUUGUACUUAAACCUCCUGCUGUGCCUCGCAUCCUAUGCUUAAUAAAAGAACAUGCUUGAAUAUCA